GUGAUCAUUUCAAACCAAGCAUCAGCAACAAUUAAAAAUAUUCACUUGGUAUCUGUAGUUUAAUAAUGGACCAACAUCAACAUUUGAAUAAAACAGCAGAGUCAGCAUCUUCAGAGAAAAAGAAAACAAGACGCUGCAAUGGAUUCAAGAUGUUCUUGGCAGCCCUGUCAUUCAGCUAUAUUGCUAAAGCACUAGGUGGAAUCAUUAUGAAAAUUUCCAUCACUCAAAUAGAAAGGAGAUUUGACAUAUCCUCUUCUCUUGCUGGUUUAAUUGAUGGAAGCUUUGAAAUUGGAAAUUUGCUUGUGAUUGUAUUUGUAAGUUACUUUGGAUCUAAACUACACAGACCGAAGUUAAUUGGAAUUGGUUGUCUCCUUAUGGGAACUGGAAGUAUUUUGACAUCUUUACCACAUUUCUUCAUGGGAUAUUAUAGGUAUUCUAAAGAAACCCAUAUUAAUCCAUCAGAAAAUUCAACAUCAAGUUUAUCAACCUGUUUAAUUAAUCAAACCUUAUCAUUCAAUGGAACAUCACCUGAGAUAGUAGAAAAAGAUUGUGUAAAGGAAUCUGGGUCACACAUGUGGAUCUAUGUCUUCAUGGGGAAUAUGCUUCGUGGCAUAGGGGAAACCCCCAUAGUACCAUUGGGGAUUUCAUACAUUGAUGAUUUUGCAAAAGAAGGACAUUCUUCCUUGUAUUUAGGUAGUUUGAAUGCAAUAGGAAUGAUUGGUCCAGUCAUUGGCUUUGCACUGGGAUCUCUGUUUGCUAAAAUGUACGUGGAUAUUGGAUAUGUAGAUCUGAGCACUAUCAGAAUAACUCCUAAGGACUCUCGUUGGGUUGGAGCUUGGUGGCUUGGUUUCCUUGUGUCUGGACUAUUUUCCAUUAUUUCUUCCAUACCAUUUUUUUUCUUGCCGAAAAAUCCAAAUAAACCACAAAAAGAAAGAAAAAUUUCACUAUCAUUGCAUGUGCUGAAAACAAAUGAUGAUAGAAAUCAAACAGCUAAUUUGACCAACCAAGGAAAAAAUGUUACCAAAAAUGUGACUGGUUUUUUCCAGUCUUUGAAAAGCAUCCUUACCAAUCCCCUGUAUGUUAUAUUUCUGCUUUUGACAUUGUUACAAGUAAGCAGCUUUAUUGGUUCUUUUACUUACGUCUUUAAAUAUAUGGAGCAACAGUACGGUCAGUCUGCAUCUCAUGCUAACUUUUUGUUGGGAAUCAUAACCAUUCCUACGGUUGCAACUGGAAUGUUUUUAGGAGGAUUUAUCAUUAAAAAAUUCAAAUUGUCUUUAGUUGGAAUUGCCAAAUUUUCAUUUCUUACUUCGAUGAUAUCCUUCUUGUUUCAACUUCUAUAUUUCCCUCUAAUCUGCGAAAGCAAAUCAGUUGCCGGCCUAACCUUGACCUAUGAUGGAAAUAAUUCAGUGGCAUCUCAUGUAGAUGUACCACUUUCUUAUUGCAACUCAGAGUGCAAUUGUGAUGAAAGUCAGUGGGAACCAGUCUGUGGGAACAAUGGAAUAACUUACCUGUCACCUUGUCUAGCAGGAUGCAAAUCCUCAAGUGGUAUUAAAAAGCAUACAGUGUUUUAUAACUGUAGUUGUGUGGAAGUAACUGGUCUCCAGAACAGAAAUUACUCAGCACACUUGGGUGAAUGCCCAAGAGAUAAUACUUGUACAAGGAAAUUUUUCAUCUAUGUUGCAAUUCAAGUCAUAAACUCUUUGUUCUCUGCAACAGGAGGUACCACAUUUAUCUUGUUGACUGUGAAGAUUGUUCAACCUGAAUUGAAAGCACUUGCAAUGGGUUUCCAGUCAAUGGUUAUAAGAACACUAGGAGGAAUUCUAGCUCCAAUAUAUUUUGGGGCUCUGAUUGAUAAAACAUGUAUGAAGUGGUCCACCAACAGCUGUGGAGCACAAGGGGCUUGUAGGAUAUAUAAUUCCGUAUUUUUUGGGAUUGUUCAACCUGAAUUGAAAGCACUUGCAAUCGGCUUCCAUUCAAUGAUUAUGCGAUCGCUAGGAGGUAUUCUAGUUCCAAUAUAUUUUGGGGCUCUGAUUGAUACAACGUGUAUGAAGUGGUCCACCAACAGCUGUGGAGCACGAGGGGCUUGUAGGAUAUAUAAUUCCACAUAUUUGGGAAGAGCCUUCUUCGGCUUGAAGGUAGCCCUAAUAUUUCCAGUACUUGUUUUACUUACUGUAUUUAUUUUUGUUGUAAGGAAAAAAUCCCAUGGAAAGGAUACCAAAGUAUUAGAAAAUGAAAGACAAGUAAUGGAUGAAGCAAACUUAGAAUUCUUAAACGACAGUGAACAUUUUGUACCUUCUGCUGAAGAACAGUAAAGCAUGUAAUUAAGAGGAGGAAAAAAAUAAUUUUGCUGCUGUUUCCAACUAAUGUAUUGAUUCCAUAAGACGUUAUUUUUGUGGUGUUCUGAGUCUUUUCACUGAGAAUUCCCACAUUCUUCACUUAUGAUGCAACAAUGAAUAAGCCUAUGAAUUUAUAAUGAAACAAACUAUAAAAAAUGGUACCCAUGGUUAGGACAUAGCUACACAAGCAUUUGUAGUUUAGAAUAUAUAAUUCAUAAAAAUUUGAAGUGAGAGGAAUAGUUAAUAUGUAAUAGAAGAAAAAGUACUUGCUCAGGUAGUUGUAACUCUUAAUAAAACCAAUGACUAGAAUACAAGUGGAAGUAAAAAGGUGGAGAUAGAUUAAUAGCCUAAAUAACGAGAGAACCUUAUGCCUUUUUUAAAACAAAACAAAACCAUUGAGACAUUUUACUUAGUCCUAAAAUCUAGCCUGGAUUUAUGCUAUAAUGAUAUCUAUUUUUCAUGUUAAAUUGUACAUUACUCAGAAAUUAUAAAUAUUAUUACUUUAUAAUUUGAAAUUGUGUUUGCUAGCCACCUUGAUGUAUUUUCUUCCAAACUCCCAUUAAGAUACUAUUGAAAAAAUAGAAAUAGUCAAAUAUUUGCAAGGUAUAAUUGUUAGGCAACAUAUUAUAGCAUGUGUUAAGUUUCUGCUAGGCCUAUGGAAAUUUUUUUUUUUAUUUUUGUUCCAUUUUUAUUCACUUUGAGGAAGUGUUGCCUUUUUUUUUGAUGUACUUAAAUGGCUAAAAUAAAAAAGACAAUCACAAGAAAAAAAAAGAAGAAAAAAUAAAAAUGAAAAUAAAAAUAAAAUAUCCAUCAAUUUUAAUUUCACUCCAGUUAGAGAAAGUAAAAGCUCUGGUCUUAGAUACAUCUCUUGUAUUUCAUCUGUAGUGAGAAGAAAGAACACUCUUCAUUGGCAAUUAUCAAAUUAUUUGUUUGAAGAGCAUUUUUCCACAUUCAGCUCCCCAUCUUCUUGCAUAAGGAAAUGGUUUAAGAAAAGCUGACUUUGACUUGAGAAACAAAAUCCAUUGAUAAGAUGUGUCUUCAUUGCAUCUGUCUGUUCUCUGGGAGAAAUAAAAUCUGUGUCACUCUCUUGCA